GCUUCCGUCGCUCCUUGCCGGGCAUAAUGGCCGCGCAGCGACCCCUGCGGGUCCUGUGCCUGGCGGGCUUCCGGCAGAGCGAGCGGGGCUUCCGUGAGAAGACCGGGGCGCUGAGGAAGGCGCUGCGGGGUCGCGCCGAGCUCGUGUGCCUCAGCGGCCCGCACCCGGUCCCCGACCCCCCGGGCCCCGAGGGCGCCAGAUCAGACUUCGGGUCCUGCCCUCCGGAGGAGCAGCCUCGAGGCUGGUGGUUUUCAGAGCAGGAGGCCGACGUUUUCUCCGCAUUGGAAGAGCCCGCCGUCUGCAGGGGCCUGGAGGAAUCACUGGGGAUGGUGGCACAGGCACUGAACAGGCUGGGGCCUUUUGACGGCCUUCUUGGUUUCAGCCAAGGGGCUGCGCUAGCAGCCCUUGUGUGUGCCCUGGGCCAGGCAGGCGAUCCCCGCUUCCCCUUGCCACGGUUUAUCCUCUUGGUGUCUGGUUUCUGUCCCCGGGGCAUUGGGUUCAAGGAAUCCAUCCUGCAAAGGCCCUUGUCAUUGCCUUCGCUCCAUGUUUUUGGGGACACUGACAAAGUCAUCCCCUCUCAGGAGAGUGUGCAACUGGCCAGCCAAUUUCCCGGAGCCAUCACCCUCACCCACUCUGGUGGCCACUUCAUUCCAGCAGCUGCACCCCAGCGUCAGGCCUACCUCAAGUUCUUGGACCAGUUUGCAGAGUGAAAGAUCAAGAAAUGUCUCUGCUCCUACAUCCAGCUCCUCUAGGGGCAGCCUCCGUCAUCCAUGCCCUCCCAGGACCCUCCACUCACUGCUGUGAGUGCGCCUCACCAGAACCAGUUAAGAGACAACUAUCAAUUCUUGAGACCCAAAUUAUAAGGGCCCUGCCCUGUACUGAAGAAAAGGGGAGCACAAGGCCUUAAUGGACAUUGACUUGUGAAAACGCAAACAUGAAUAUGGUUGGAGAGCCCUGGAUUAGGAGGGUGACAUGGGGAAGGCAGAGGCUGGCACCAUGGUGACUGCCACAUAAUAAAGUGGUGAUUUGGA